AAAGGAAGAAGAGUCCACCUUGCGACCGUAUCCGCUAGCGCGGCCUGGGAUGCGCUUGGGCUCCCUGGUGAAAAAGCAAAAUAUAAAAUUCGAUUCAAACUGUGAUUACAUCUAUGGAAAAUACAGCCUUUGCCGACCACCCUCUUUGUCCCGCCGCCCUCCGUGCUCCCCUCUGUUUUGUGUACGGAGUUUCUUACUUUGUACAAGUCCGCAGCCGCUUAUGUUACAGCCCCGAGGCCAGAUGCGUUUAAAAUCGAGGAGUUCUCGGAGUUUGGAAAGUUCGUUCCCACAUGCAGGGCAGCACAAGGAGAAUGGGCGUCAUGACUGAUGUCCACCGGCGCUUCCUCCAGUUGCUGAUGACCCAUGGCGUGCUAGAGGAAUGGGACGUGAAGCGCUUGCAGACGCACUGCUACAAGGUCCAUGACCGCAAUGCCACCGUAGAUAAGUUGGAGGACUUCAUCAACAACAUUAACAGUGUCUUGGAGUCCUUGUAUAUUGAGAUAAAGAGAGGAGUCACGGAAGAUGAUGGGAGACCCAUUUAUGCGUUGGUGAAUCUUGCUACAACUUCAAUUUCCAAAAUGGCUACGGAUUUUGCAGAGAAUGAACUGGAUUUGUUUAGAAAGGCUCUGGAACUGAUUAUUGACUCAGAAACCGGCUUUGCGUCUUCCACAAACAUAUUGAACCUGGUUGAUCAACUUAAAGGCAAGAAGAUGAGGAAGAAGGAAGCGGAGCAGGUGCUGCAGAAGUUUGUUCAAAACAAGUGGCUGAUUGAGAAGGAAGGGGAGUUCACCCUGCACGGCCGGGCCAUCCUGGAGAUGGAGCAAUACAUCCGGGAGACGUACCCCGACGCGGUGAAGAUCUGCAAUAUCUGUCACAGCCUCCUCAUCCAGGGUCAAAGCUGCGAAACCUGUGGGAUCAGGAUGCACUUACCCUGCGUGGCCAAGUACUUCCAGUCGAAUGCUGAACCGCGCUGCCCCCACUGCAACGACUACUGGCCCCACGAGAUCCCAAAAGUCUUCGACCCUGAGAAGGAGAGGGAGUCUGGUGUCUUGAAAUCGAACAAAAAGUCCCUGCGGUCCAGGCAGCAUUAGCCAUCGUGCCCUGCUGAGGGGCUGGCUGCCUUGAGUGGCCUGAUCGCCACAGCCCUUCUUGGAAGAAAGGCGUCCGUGUUUCAGGUUCCACGCGAGUCACCUCUUUCGUCUUAAUGUUCACCGUCCACAGCUUUGGAAUAAACCAUCCUGGGAAGUUGCUGCA